AGUUAACCUGCUGGAGCUCAUCAGGCUUGCUCAGAGCCCCUGCACCAACUCACCCUGUACCCUCUCUCCUUCUUCGUUAGUCUUCUUUCCCCCUUUUCCCUCCUCUGUCUGUGCCUAUCCCCCGACUUUUGCAUCUGACCAAAGGACGAAUGAGGGAGACGUUCCUGCAGAUCGGGGCAGCAACUUUCCUCAGCUGGUCUCUGGGCUCCGGGAGCCAGAGAGCGCUGAUCCUCCGCGGUCUGCGGCCCAUGGAAGAGGAGGAGGAGGAGCCGUGAUGGGCUAGCGACAGCACUGAGGAGCCCCGAGAGAGCUCAGCCUUGCCAGCCAGCUCCGCGGUCCCACGCGGGUUCCCUCGAGCUCGCUCCGUGGGGAGCGCGCAGCGUGCUUGGAACCGGAGCAUCCAGAGAGGAUGAGGCGGGGACCCGGCCCAAGUUGGGUGCAUCUCUCGGGCGUCCGGCAGCGGCUGUAUCUCGGCAUGAAUUAAGAAGCUAGGAAGAUGGAGCACGGCACACUCCUCGCCCAGCCCGGGCUCUGGACCAGGGACACCAGCUGGGCACUCCUCUAUUUCCUCUGCUAUAUCCUCCCUCAGACCGCCCCGCAAGUACUCAGGAUCGGAGGGAUUUUUGAAACAGUGGAAAAUGAGCCUGUUAAUGUUGAAGAAUUAGCUUUCAAGUUUGCAGUCACCAGCAUUAACAGAAACCGAACCCUGAUGCCUAACACCACAUUAACCUAUGACAUCCAGAGAAUUAACCUUUUUGAUAGUUUUGAAGCCUCGCGGAGAGCAUGUGACCAGCUGGCUCUUGGUGUGGCUGCUCUCUUUGGCCCUUCCCAUAGCUCCUCCGUCAGUGCUGUGCAGUCUAUUUGCAAUGCUCUCGAAGUUCCACACAUACAGACCCGCUGGAAACACCCCUCGGUGGACAACAAAGAUUUGUUUUACAUCAACCUUUACCCAGAUUAUGCAGCUAUCAGCAGGGCGAUCCUGGAUCUGGUCCUCUAUUACAACUGGAAAACAGUGACAGUGGUGUAUGAAGACAGCACAGGUCUAAUUCGUCUACAAGAGCUCAUCAAAGCUCCCUCCAGAUAUAAUAUUAAAAUCAAAAUCCGCCAGCUGCCCUCUGGGAAUAAAGAUGCCAAGCCUUUACUCAAGGAGAUGAAGAAAGGCAAGGAGUUCUAUGUGAUAUUUGAUUGUUCACAUGAAACAGCCGCUGAAAUCCUUAAGCAGAUUCUGUUCAUGGGCAUGAUGACCGAGUACUAUCACUACUUUUUCACAACCCUGGACUUAUUUGCUUUGGAUCUGGAACUCUAUAGGUACAGUGGCGUAAACAUGACCGGGUUUCGGCUGCUUAACAUUGACAACCCUCACGUGUCAUCCAUCAUUGAGAAGUGGUCCAUGGAGAGACUGCAGGCCCCACCCAGGCCCGAGACUGGCCUUUUGGAUGGCAUGAUGACAACUGAAGCGGCUCUGAUGUACGAUGCUGUGUACAUGGUGGCCAUUGCCUCGCACCGGGCAUCCCAGCUGACCGUCAGCUCCCUGCAGUGCCAUAGACAUAAGCCAUGGCGCCUCGGACCCAGAUUUAUGAACCUGAUCAAAGAGGCCCGGUGGGAUGGCUUGACUGGGCAUAUCACCUUUAAUAAAACCAAUGGCUUGAGGAAGGAUUUUGAUCUGGACAUUAUUAGUCUCAAAGAGGAAGGAACUGAAAAGGCUGCUGGCGAAGUGUCUAAACACUUGUAUAAAGUGUGGAAGAAGAUUGGGAUUUGGAAUUCCAACAGUGGGCUUAACAUGACGGACAGCAACAAAGACAAGUCCAGCAAUAUCACUGAUUCAUUGGCCAACAGAACACUCAUUGUCACCACCAUUCUGGAAGAACCCUAUGUUAUGUACAGGAAAUCUGAUAAGCCUCUAUAUGGAAAUGACAGAUUUGAAGGAUAUUGCCUAGACCUGUUGAAAGAAUUGUCAAACAUCCUGGGUUUCAUUUAUGAUGUUAAACUAGUUCCCGAUGGCAAAUAUGGGGCCCAGAAUGACAAAGGGGAGUGGAACGGGAUGGUUAAAGAACUCAUAGAUCACAGGGCUGACCUGGCAGUGGCUCCUCUUACCAUCACCUACGUGCGGGAGAAAGUCAUUGACUUCUCCAAACCCUUCAUGACCCUAGGCAUCAGCAUUCUCUACCGGAAGCCCAAUGGUACCAAUCCAGGCGUUUUCUCCUUCCUCAACCCCCUGUCUCCAGAUAUUUGGAUGUAUGUGCUCUUAGCCUGCUUGGGAGUCAGCUGUGUACUCUUUGUGAUUGCAAGGUUUACACCCUACGAGUGGUAUAACCCCCACCCAUGCAACCCUGACUCAGACGUGGUGGAAAACAAUUUUACUUUACUAAAUAGUUUCUGGUUUGGAGUUGGAGCUCUCAUGCAGCAAGGAUCAGAGCUGAUGCCCAAAGCUCUAUCGACCAGAAUAGUUGGAGGGAUAUGGUGGUUUUUCACCCUAAUCAUCAUUUCAUCCUACACGGCCAAUCUGGCUGCCUUCUUGACAGUAGAGAGAAUGGAAUCCCCCAUAGAUUCGGCAGAUGAUCUGGCAAAGCAAACCAAGAUAGAAUAUGGGGCGGUUAGAGAUGGAUCAACAAUGACCUUCUUCAAGAAAUCAAAAAUCUCCACCUAUGAGAAGAUGUGGGCUUUCAUGAGCAGCAGGCAGCAGACCGCCCUGGUAAGAAACAGUGAUGAGGGGAUCCAGAGAGUGCUCACCACAGACUACGCGCUGCUGAUGGAGUCCACCAGCAUUGAGUAUGUGACGCAGAGAAACUGCAACCUCACUCAGAUCGGGGGCCUCAUUGACUCCAAAGGUUACGGAGUGGGAACACCUAUUGGUUCUCCUUACCGGGAUAAAAUUACUAUUGCUAUUCUUCAACUCCAAGAAGAAGGGAAGCUGCAUAUGAUGAAAGAGAAGUGGUGGCGUGGGAAUGGCUGCCCCGAGGAAGACAACAAAGAAGCCAGUGCCCUGGGAGUGGAAAAUAUUGGAGGCAUCUUCAUUGUUCUGGCUGCCGGACUGGUCCUUUCUGUAUUUGUAGCUAUUGGAGAAUUCAUAUACAAAUCACGGAAGAAUAAUGAUAUUGAACAGGUGAGUCAUCUCUUUCUAGGACUGGUUAGUUUAUAGUUUGCAUUAUCUGUCUUAAGUUUGGGGGUUUUUAAGGAUGUUUGCUCUUUUUCAGUCUAUUGAAUUAGAUGCCCAGAAGAGCCAUUUUUGAGUUAGAGCAGAGAGCUAUUGAAUCCCUGCCAGGUGCUGUGGGCACUGCAGGUCCAUCAUUUAUUAACGACAAGGAAGGGGCUUAUACACUAAAUCCAAUUAGCAUUAUUUGGAAAGACAGUGCAGAAAUUCCAAACUCAGUUAAUUUUUGAACUGUUGUUUGCUCGUAAGAUAGAAACCCUAGAUGGAAAAAGGCAAAAAUAAAUCCAAAAUUGGAAAAGAUAUAAAAAGAUAUUUAACAGAAAUGUUACCAGCCCUUAAGUAUAGAUUCUGAGCACAUGUACUAAUGCAAAACAAUUUAUAUAAAUAUGUAAAAGUCAUACUACGAAAUUGAACACUUCUAUCAAAGUAAGAUUUGUAAAAGGAUAUAUCACCUCAAAUUUUUUUUUGCCAGGAAUGUCAUAAACAAUACAAAAUGAAAAUGCAAUGUAUAUGAGACUUUAUUUUUCUAAAUUGUGUUUGGGAUUAUAGGACAACUUUAGUAGUUGACCAUUUUUGCCUACUACUUUUAUUUCUGAAGGAAAUCACACCAUUUUUGAAGGAAAUCAACUUACACUCUUUUGAAAAGGCUGAUUGUGAUUUAAGAUAAUUCCUUCAUAACCAUGCUAGAAUAAACAAAAUAUAAAGUUUAUGGUCAUCAUAGUGAAUCAGGCUCUGCUUUGAAUUUUUAAAUAUUGUUAGAAUUUUAAGACUAUGACUAUUAAUGACAGAGCCAGUUUAAUGCUCUCCUGUCAUCUUGAAAUUCUAAAUAAUUUUUGAACAAAGUGUCCCAUAUUUUCAUUUCGCACUGGACCCUGCAAAUUAUGUGGCUGGUUCUGAUUAAUAAUCUGAUAAUAGAUCCACUUUCUUUAAGUGGAAGCCCUCCUUAAGGGCCCAAAACUGGGGAUGAUUCAUUAUAACCUGGUUUCACAUGAAAAUCUUCCCCAGAAUUACAAGGCAACUAUGACAACAAUGAACACCCCUUUCCAAAGCUCUUGUUAUAAGAAGCUGUUUCUUUAAUUCAAAGGGAGAAUGAACUGAUCUGCUUUAACUUUCAAUUUGCUCUUGAGGUGUCUUGUUUUAUGCAACUAAUUUGGAAAAUAAAAGCUUGUAUAUAUGAUGCUUUAAUGUGCUUUUCAUAGUUGCCAGCUUCAUGUGAUGUAAAUUUUCAUUUAAACAUUCAUUCUUGCUUCUGAUUUAUUCAUUUUUCUAUAUUUUUUUCUCAUUUCUUUUGCAUGCAAGGCUUUUUGUUUCUUUUAUGGACUGCAAUGUAAGCAAACCCAUCCAACCAACUCCACUUCUGGAACUACUUUAUCUACGGAUUUAGAAUGUGGUAAAUUAAUUCGAGAGGAGAGAGGGAUUCGAAAACAGUCCUCAGUUCAUACUGUGUAAUCAGUUUAAAAAAAAAAAAAAAGAUGUGCCCAGUAGAAAAUGUUUUUGCUAAUUGGUGUUGUUGAUAUUUGUAUUUGCUAAGCAUAAAUAGCCACAAUUCUCUAUUCCUUUAGGAUAGCAAAACUCAUGUAUUCUAGACAUUGAAAUGAAUACACUGGAAAGAUACUUGCACUGUAUGUUGAAGCAGGGGCAUAUUAGGGGUAUAAAGACUUCUAGAAAUGUGUAUUUACAGGAAUCUUCUCUGUCCCACUCAUCAUCUUAGUUCUAUCUUCAUGCAUUAAAAAUAAGUAACUCUUCCUUCAUGAAAAAGGAGAUUCAGACUUUCAACAGGGCAAAGCAUGGAAACACGAUGCUAAUUCUAUGGACUUCUUUUCAUCUUUGUGAACUUUGUUCCCUCCUCUUUUCUUCUCCCUGUCUCAUAUAUUGUGUAGAUCUGCGUAUUUUCAAACUACCCAAAACCCUUACCUUUUCAACAGUACACACAUAACUCCAUAACAAUGUUAAUUUUUAAUUGAAACUGAUUCCACGAUUUAAAAUGUAUUAUUUACACAAAGACUCAAAAGUGUCUUAGCAUUUAAAGAUUUAAAAACCGUGAUCCACAGAAAGAAAACUAAACUUGAAACCUCUGGUGUCACAGAAGAGCACUAGCUAUGUUGAACAUCACUCAUGGAAACAGAACACAGUCAAGAAUAAUUCCUGGGCAGAAAUUCAUUAACCUCAAACUCUCAAAUAACAUUUACUUGUAGAAUUUAACAGUCUUCUGUAGGUUCUGAGUCUCUAAGGAAUGGUGAUAUUUUUCAAGCUAUAUAGUACUUCUUUGAAGAUCCCAGCAAAGUCCUAAGCUAUGUACUAAUUCAUUUCUAUUUACCACUCACUUUGCAUUGAUGAACAUCUUUCUACGAGAUGUUAUUUCACUUCCUUCCCACUUACCCUAGAUAGAGGGGUUGUUCUUGGAACAAUCUUUUCUGAACAUCACCAUUUUCACAGUUAUUUCUUUGGAUCCAUCAUUAUUAUUAAUUCAUUUAAAGUAUUCUGGGGAAACGGGCAAGAAGGAAAAAAUAAAGGAAAGAAUGUCCAUACACAUUAGUUACAGAUCUCUGUAGAUUCAUUUUCCAUCUGCAUUCAAAGUGCUGUAAAUAAUUUCCAUGCUAACUCAACCAGGUGACAUAAAAAACCUCUUGCACAUUUAAUUUGUUGUGACAGAGAAUAUCUGAUGAUUCCUCACUAGUGAAUAAGAGAGUUGAAGGUGUGUUUCAUCUUUUCUAAAUAUGGGAUCAGUUGGUCUUUAUUCUUUUCUUAAUGGGAUUAUCUUUUGACAUAUCAAGAAAUCCCCUAAAGCACUUCCUUGAAGUAGAGAUAUGCCAUCUGUGCAAUCAUACAGCAUUUUACCUUCUCUUUGCUUAGCUUUAAAUGGCUCCCAGUUUUGGAAGCCACAGGCUUCUCCAAUCAACUGUAUAUUUCUCCAGUAAAGCAUAUUCAGGAAAGUUGACUAGUUGAUUCUUAUCCUGAUUGUUUCUCAGCUUUGCUUCCUUCUUUAAAGAAAUGUACUCAGAAGAAAAUAUCAUAAAUUACACUAACAUUGUUUUAUUAUUAUUAAACUAGAAGCAACAUACUAUUUGUCCCAGGUCAGAGUUCACAUUUUCAUAAUCAAUAGAAUCAGAUGUUGGGAUGAAUAUGACAUUAUUCUUAGUUUCAUAUUUCAUGGAUUCAGUAUAUAGAAACCACAAAUUUCCUAAGUUUACUCUCCCAAAGACAAUUUAAUAAACCAAAAAUGCUACCAAAAGAGUUCAAGUGUGAUUGAUGAAGUAUUGACAAUCAAAAUUAACAAUAACUGACAAAACUUAACUUUCUGCAGAGACUAUUACUUAAAAGUGUAAUUCAGAGAUUUGGAUAAAGAAAUGAUCUCUUUCAAAAGUUAAUAUUUCUAUACUACUUUAGACUGUAUACUACCUAAUUCUGACAUUUAUGUAUUAUUUUAUAGUUUUCAAAAUGUUUUCACAUACAUUACAUUUGAUCCUUUCAACAAUUUAAAUUCAGCUUUACUAACAGAGAAGUAGAUAUCCAUCAUCGACCUGUAGUUAUAGAUUUUAGAAGCAGAAGAAAAUUUUCUAAAACAGCCAAACUUAGAUUCAGGUUCUAGCAGAGCCACAUGCUGAAUGACUGCAGGCAAGUUACCAAACUUCUCAGUCUCAAUUUCUUAAUAUGUAGCAGUGGGACAAAAUUUCUGGAACACAAAGUUUUGUAGGGGUGUUUUUCAAAAUGUGUUCAAUUGGCAAAUGUUUCUCAAAUAGAAUUUUCAUAGUUAAAUAACCCAUAGAGCGUCACUCUAAAUGUUCCUUUACUACAUGCUAUCUCAGUGUGCGUCACAAGUUUUUGCGCAUUGAGAAUUUUCAACAAAGUAGAAAAGUAUUCAGCACUUCUGAAGCCUAUUAGAUUGCAGAUUUUUUUCCCCACAGCAUCUUGACAGACCAGUGUUCCACAGAUCAUCCUCAAGGGAACACAGGUAUGAUCAUGUGAAUCUCAUCCCAUAAUAGUGUACAAGACAUCUUGCAUUGUGCUUGGCACAUAGUAGCCACUCAAUAAAUAAUUAUGUAUUCUUUAGAGUAAA